AGCCACCCCCUGACGGCUUCCCCACGGGAGGACGCGAGGCCCCGGCCCAGCCAUGGCCCCCUGGCGCAAAGCUGACAAGGAGCGGCACGGCGUGGCCAUAUACAACUUCCAAGGCAGCGGAGCCCCCCAGCUCUCCCUGCAGAUCGGCGAUGUGGUGCGAAUACAGGAGACGUGUGGAGACUGGUAUAGGGGAUACCUCAUAAAGCACAAAAUGUUACAGGGCAUUUUUCCUAAGUCAUUUAUCCACAUCAAGGAAGUGACAGUUGAGAAAAGAAGAAAUACUGAGAACAUCAUUCCUGCAGAAAUUCCUCUGGCACAAGAAGUGACAACGACACUUUGGGAAUGGGGAAGCAUCUGGAAACAACUCUAUGUGGCCAGCAAAAAGGAGCGUUUUCUCCAGGUGCAGUCCAUGAUGUACGAUCUGAUGGAGUGGAGGUCCCAGCUUCUCUCAGGAACCUUACCCAAGGAUGAGCUGAAGGAACUGAAGCAGAAAGUCACGUCCAAAAUUGACUAUGGCAACAAAAUCCUUGAGCUUGAUUUGAUUGUCAGAGAUGAAGACGGAAAUAUCUUGGACCCUGAUAAUACCAGUGUCAUCAGCUUGUUCCAUGCACAUGAGGAAGCAACUGAUAAAAUCACAGAGCGUAUCAAAGAAGAAAUGUCAAAAGACCAGCCAGAUUAUGCAAUGUAUUCCCGGAUCUCCUCAUCCCCCACCCAUAGCCUCUAUGUGUUUGUGAGAAACUUUGUGUGCAGAAUUGGGGAAGAUGCUGAGCUCUUCAUGUCUCUCUACGACCCCAACAAGCAAACGGUCAUAAGUGAGAACUACCUAGUGCGAUGGGGCAGCCGGGGCUUCCCUAAGGAGAUUGAGAUGCUCAACAAUCUGAAGGUGGUCUUCACGGAUCUUGGAAACAAAGACCUCAACAGGGAUAAAAUUUACUUGAUUUGUCAAAUAGUCCGGGUCGGCAAGAUGGAUCUUAAGGAUACUGGUGCAAAGAAGUGCACGCAGGGACUGAGGAGGCCCUUUGGGGUGGCAGUUAUGGAUAUAACAGACAUCAUCAAGGGGAAAGCAGAGAGUGAUGAAGAAAAGCAGCACUUCAUUCCUUUUCACCCGGUUACAGCUGAGAAUGACUUCCUACACAGCCUGCUGGGCAAAGUCAUAGCCUCCAAGGGGGACAGUGGAGGGCAAGGCCUCUGGGUGACCAUGAAGAUGCUGGUGGGUGACAUCAUUCAGAUUCGCAAGGACUAUCCACACCUGGUGGACAGGACCACCGUGGUGGCCAGGAAGCUGGGAUUCCCAGAGAUCAUCAUGCCAGGGGAUGUCAGGAACGACAUCUACAUUACUCUCUUACAAGGUGACUUUGACAAGUACAACAAGACCACACAGAGGAAUGUGGAAGUCAUCAUGUGUGUGUGCGCGGAGGAUGGCAAAACGCUGCCUAAUGCAAUUUGCGUGGGAGCAGGGGACAAGCCCAUGAAUGAGUAUCGCUCCGUUGUGUACUAUCAAGUCAAACAGCCACGCUGGAUGGAAACAGUCAAGGUGGCUGUCCCUAUUGAAGACAUGCAGAGGAUCCAUCUGCGAUUCAUGUUUCGACAUCGGUCAUCUCUGGAAUCUAAAGAUAAAGGAGAAAAGAACUUUGCCAUGUCCUAUGUGAAGCUGAUGAAAGAAGAUGGGACUACUCUACACGAUGGAUUCCAUGACUUAGUUGUCCUCAAGGGGGACAGCAAGAAGAUGGAGGAUGCCAGCGCAUACCUGACCCUUCCUUCUUAUCGACACCAUGUGGAAAACAAGGGGGCCACGCUGAGCAGGAGCUCCAGCAGUGUUGGGGGGCUUUCUGUCAGCUCCCGGGAUGUGUUCUCCAUUUCCACCCUGGUGUGCUCCACAAAGCUCACUCAGAAUGUGGGCUUGCUGGGUUUGCUGAAGUGGCGUAUGAAGCCUCAACUGCUACAGGAGAAUUUAGAAAAGUUGAAGAUUGUGGAUGGAGAGGAAGUGGUGAAGUUUCUCCAGGAUACUCUGGAUGCCCUCUUCAACAUCAUGAUGGAGCAUUCUCAAAGUGAUGAAUAUGACAUCCUCGUCUUUGAUGCCUUGAUUUACAUAAUAGGACUCAUUGCAGACCGGAAAUUUCAGCAUUUCAACACCGUUCUGGAGGCUUACAUCCAACAGCAUUUCAGUGCGACCUUGGCUUACAAGAAAUUGAUGACAGUGCUGAAGACUUACUUGGAUACCUCCAGCAGAGGGGAGCAAUGUGAGCCAAUCCUAAGAACGCUGAAGGCUUUGGAAUAUGUGUUCAAGUUCAUUGUUCGGUCGAGGACAUUAUUUUCACAGCUUUAUGAAGGCAAAGAACAGAUGGAGUUUGAAGAAUCCAUGAGACGGCUCUUUGAAUCCAUCAACAAUCUGAUGAAAAGUCAAUACAAAACUACCAUCCUUUUGCAGGUGGCGGCUUUGAAAUACAUCCCAUCUGUCCUGCAUGAUGUAGAAAUGGUCUUUGAUGCGAAGUUACUCAGCCAACUCCUGUAUGAGUUCUACACCUGCAUCCCUCCUGUGAAACUCCAGAAGCAGAAAGUACAGUCUAUGAAUGAGAUAGUCCAGAGCAACCUCUUUAAAAAGCAAGAAUGCCGGGACAUUCUGCUUCCUGUCAUCACCAAAGAGCUGAAGGAGCUGCUGGAGCAGAAGGAUGACAUGCAACACCAGGUCCUGGAGAGGAAGUACUGCGUUGAAUUGCUCAACAGCAUCUUGGAAGUCCUUAGCUACCAGGAUGCGGCCUUCACCUACCACCAUAUCCAGGAGAUCAUGGUCCAGCUGCUGCGGACAGUGAACCGGACAGUCAUCACCAUGGGCCGGGAUCACAUUCUGAUUCAUAGGGGUCUUCCAGAAAAAUCGAUGAGUCUAGAUUUUUGAGGACUGCUGUGAUAUUCUUUUAAAGAUGAAGACUGUAAUCAAGCCAAAUUUUCCCAAACACAUUCCAUGGAACACUAAGCACGUGGAUCAACAGUUUUGUAGUCAAAUAUUUGGAAAAUGUUGCCUCUUUCCUCCUCUUCGUAGGAAUUUGCUGUGGCUCUAAGCAUUCCUGCAUCCAGUAAAGAUGUCUGUUUAACUUUGUUUAACCCAGUGUUUUCCAGUUUCACCUCAUCAAAGAGCCCUUACAGAGCUGUGGAGAGGAGCACUUGGGAGAAGCCAGUUUUGGAGAUGGGAUUGCAUCCCAGGAGUACAUUGAAAUGAUUGCUUUCUUGAGGAUUAGGGCCCACUGAUAAGAACAGGCUGUAAGCAGUGUUGUGACAGUCUUCUCCCAGAGCUCUUAAUCGAACUUUUAAGUUUCUCAAUUGAAUAGUGCACAAAUACAAUAUUUUACCCUUUUACUGAAGGAACAUAGUAAAUAAUACUGUGAUAGCCCCUUGACAGUAGAAAGAUGAUCUUUUAAAAAAAUGCUCCAGAGAGGUUGGAGGAGAGAAUUACUUUUAUCUGUGUCUAUCAGAAUCCCAUGUACAUCCUGGUCCUGGGCAAAUAUUAUUUUAAGAGCUUUUCCAUGACUCAAAUACCUUCUUUCUAUUCUGCUCAUUUCCUUUUCUUUUUAGCCUUAAUGCCAUUCCACAUUUGAGAGAGAACGUUAACAUAAACUGCAGUAAUGUCAGUCAUCAAUAUUUGCAUAGCUAGGGUGCAGCUUUUGGAAGAAGCUCUCCAGAAAAAAUUACAGUACAGUGUGCACAUUGCCUAAAGGUAUUUAUUGCUUCCAAAGAAUGAAUUAUCUCAUCUUAUGGAGGAAAAGAUGAAGGCUCAGAGAAGAUGAGCCCUAAUUUAUGCAGAACCCCUGAUAAUAUUCAUCUGGAAUACCAAGAAAUAAUGUUAAUACAUAAAAAUAAUGUAAUGUAAAUCAUGUUAUGCACUGCAGCAGUUAGCUGGAAGAUCUGGAACUGAUUCACCUGGUCAGUUUAGAGCUUUCUGAACUCCCUUGGUAUUGUAUCCAGACUGGGCUUGAUACAUUUAAUUAUCUAAGUAAAGUAGAUCUUGGCCAUCACCUUUGAAUAAUACCAACAAUGAGAAAAAUAACCGUUAAUGGUUGAGGAUUUGCAGUUUAGAGAAUAUCACCUACAUUAUCUUUCUAAGCUGGUGGAGUUACCUCAUUUAACAGAUUUAUAGUGCUCAGAGAGGUUAAGUGAUUUGUAUAUGGUCACACAGCUUAAUGUAUACUUGAGCUGGAGCCAGAUCCUAACCCCUUGUAUCUCCCUUAAAUUGUGCUGUCUCAUUCCACAGAGCUCCUCAGGCAAAGCUGUUUGAUUGGAUAUAACCUACAUUGUUUGAGUAUCUGAUACAUUCUGGGUGGUUUUCCAAGGGGAAUUCUUUGAAAGGGAGCUUGAAAUUUGUAUGUUGAAGUUAGAUAACCUCUUUAUUUAACAAACACCUGUACAGUACAGUGUUUAUUGUCAUUACAGGCAAGCUUCUAAGCACUUUGUAAAUAUCGAAUUGUGAAUUUCUCUUAUCGGUCCCACAGACAGAUAUAAUUUUACCGUAUUUCACAGAUGUGGAAACUAAUAUCAGAGGCUAAAUAAUUCCCUGGGGGACACAGAGCCACCACCUCAUGGAACCAGGAUUGUGCCUAGGCUCUCAGGCUCCAAGGCCUAUGCUCCUCACCUCUGUGCUGGGUUCCUUCUCCUUCUAAAUUCUCUGUUUACACAAGCAUGGGACUGGGUAGAAAAACUGGAUGGAGGGUGAUUCAGAUUGAGAUGUUUUCUUGGUGUAAACAUGAGAUGUCUGGGUGGUAAGCUUAUAUGAAUGGUUUUUACUUUUUUCUUUGUACUUUCAUAUAUUUCCUAAAUUUCCUACAAUAUUUAUGUGUUACUUUCCUAAUAAUGAAGGGGCAUACGCAGAAAACACAUUGGCUCUAGUAUAGGAUUUCAGCCUUUAUAGAUGUUGAUGCUGACUUAUUAGCAACCUAUUUGUUAGCAGCACAUGCGUGCGUGUGCAUGCACGUGGGCACACACACACACACACACACACACACACUCUUUGCAGGGGAAUUUUGAGCCAGAAAUUUAUCUGUAGGCCCAUAUUCAUUCCUUUUUGCACAUUUCUAUUGUGACCUUGGGCACGUCUCUAUCCCUCUUUGAGCCACUGUUUUCUCAUCUGAUAAAAGAAGGAUAAUAUUGCUUCAAAGAAGGUUAAUAGGACUAAGUAAGGCACUGAAUAUGCAUGUAUUUUAUAAGUUUUAAAGUGCCUUAAAAAUGUGAGUAACUGUGUUUAGGUAAAAACAUAUAUGGCAUGUUUCUUAAAGUUUCUCUUCUCUGUUAUUUGCAUAGAUGUUAUGCAACUUGUGUUGUAGAUAGUUUGCCAAGGAGAAUUUUAUCCUGCAGGCCUCAGCCAGUCAGUAUAUGAGCUAAGAUGGAAGUUUUGUGGGAUAAGCAAUCUGCUGCUCCCUUGGAGAAUUCUCUAAAUUUGCAAGUAGAAACAUUGCGGUUGGCAAAAUGGAGCUGGAUUAAUAACGUUUAUCAUUCAGGUGGAGGCUUUGUGUUUGCAAAGGGCCUGGUAAUUGGUAAUUAGCUGAUGCCCCUUGUCUCCUCCUGCCACCCUCUUCCUCCCUGCCCUGCUGUGCCCCCUGGAAUCCAGAGGCAGAGGCACCUGCAUGCUCCCAGUCUGCUUCUCCCUGCACAGUGCCUGGAAAGUCCCAGGGGACCACAGCCAUCUGACAAGUUGGUACUGGGUUGAGUUACACCAGCCACACACACUAGCUCUGGCCCUGAGCUGGGAGUAAAUGAGGUCAGGCCAAGAGACAUCAAGCUUCAAACAUAUAUUUUCAAAAUAAAUAGGAAGUCUCUGUCCUCAUACUCUUUCCCUGUCACCUUUGCUCCCUAAAAGUCUAACCUCUUUUUAGUCAGUUUCCUGGUAUCCAAAGGCCCAUUUUACUUCCUCCAACCAUCCUGUCAGCAAAUCACAUUUCCCUGUUGUGUUUUCUCCAGUAGAAAGGACUUUUCUCAUUUAUUUGUUCCUGAGAAGAAUUAGGAAUCUGAGAAUCUUGAUGAUCUUUUGGCUGCUUCUUGGGUAGCAAUUUAGACUCUCACUGAACACCCAUCUCAUCUCUUCAGAGCUAUUCAAUCAUGCUGAAGUUCAUUUGAACAAACUAAGACUUCCUAUUAGCAACCCCAUCCUGCUUAAAAAAUGGAGAUUCCCCUCUGCCAUUAAAGCAGAUCUGAGAGGCUUUUUUUGAAGGAGGGCUGAAAGUUGAAUAAUUAACAGGACAUUUCUUUUCCAACCCUUCUUUUCUUUUCUUUUUUCAUCAAUCUGAAGUAUCCUGGGACGCUCUUUGGCCUGGCACAUGGGUAGGUAGGCAUAUUGUCAAAGAUUGAGCUGCAGUUUUUCAAUUUGUGACUUCCCUGAUAACUACUUCCUCUAGAAGUCCCCAGAAAUGAAAAUGGGAGUGUGUGUCCAGGCACAAUUGCUUCUCCCAGUCUUCCUGGGGAUGUUCCAAUCUUGUCAACCAGUUUUCAGUUUUGUUUCAGAGUAUUGACUCAAGUAAUUAAAUCAUCAAUAAUAUUAGACUUCCCUUUUUCCUUUUUAAUUUUUCUUUCUCUAUUAUUCUUUUUCUUCACUAUCCACCCCAACCCCCCAUUCAUCUGUUCUUUUUAUGGAAGGCCAAAAAGUGUAAUACAUGGUAAAGAGGGGAAAGGGGACUCUGUAGUAGGGAGCUGAGGACUAGUUCAGUCAGGCAGCCCUAGCUUAGCUUCAGUUUCCUUAUCUGUAAAGUGGAGAAGUCAAACCUGCCUUGAGGGCAGGUGACUGAAACCCUGCAGGUAAGACCCUAGGACAGAUGGGUCCUGGUAAGAGCAUCGUCUUGUUGAGAGGCUGAGGUGGGCAGAUCACAAGGUCAGGCGUUAAAGACCAGCCUGGCCAACAUGGUGAAACCCCAUCUUUACUAAAAUUACAAAAAUUAACUGAGCGUGGUGUUGUGCACCUGUAAUCCCAGCUACUUGGGAGGCUGAGGCAGAAGAAUCGCUUGAACCCAGGAGGUGGAGAUUGCAAUGAGCUAAGAUCAGGCCACUGAACUCCAGCCUGGGCGACAGAGCAAGACUCUGUCUUAAAAAAAAAAAAAAAAAAAAAAAAAAGCAUUGUCCUGGGGUGUAAUCCCAGCAGCUCUGCCAUUGAUUGGUUGUGUGACCUGUGGGACUUCUGUAGUUCAGUUUCUUCAUCUGUAGAACGGAGUGACAAUAGCACCUGUCAUAUAGGGUUGUGUGUUGGGAGCAUUAAAAGAGAUCAUGUAAAGUGCUUUCCAGGAUGCCAGACCAAUAAUGGUGAGUCCUUCAUACAUAUUAUCUAUUGCUGCUAUUAUCACUGUUUCUGGAAUUUAACAAUUUCUGGUUCCCUGGGGAGAAGAUGUUCCCUGGCAGCUGGGCCUGUUUUAGGUCUUGUGUUUCCCGCAGAGACUCUAGGGAAAUUCUUAAAGGGGCUUUGUGAGUAUCAUCUCUGAGCAUAACUGUGUGCCCAGGAGCUCGCAACACACCCCUCAUUCCAUGGCAGGAUGUCGUCAGCUCUGGUUAGUCUCUGAGUCCAUUGCUUAGAGCUGAGCUUAGAAAAGAGAAUUUCUCUCUUAGAGACAAGUGGGAUGCUGUGGGAAAACAUAGAUCUGGGAAGCCAGUCAGGCCAAAGGGAUCCAGGAGUAGGAGUUCCUAUAGUCGGCAUGGAUGUGGAUAGGUAGACGCAGGCCCAGUGCCUGACUUGGGGACCACGGGGAAGCCACUCACCUGAUUGUCUCUCACCUGCCACCUGCAGACCCUGCUCCUUACUUGCUGUUUGGGAAAUAUUGUCGCUUUGCAUAGGAUGGCACUGUUCUUACUUUUGAUGAAUGUCUGAAAAAUGAACUUCUUAUCCUCUACCUUUUUCAACUGCCAUAUACAUGCUGGCAUUACUGUUAACAAAUAGGCCCUUUUCCCUGAUCACAUGAGCCUCGGAUUAUGGUCUGCAUUGAUCUUCUGUGAGCUCAGGUGGCCAUGUUCAAAGAAAGCUUUGUGAACAUGAUGACUGAGAAAGAUGAAUCUGGGUGCCGCAUGAGGCUGGAAGGUGGGGGCAGUGAUGUGGCACAUCAGCUCACUCAGGCAGGACAGAAUAGGGUUUAAGCAAAGAAUGCAUUAGAAUGCAUUAUGCCAUACGUCACCCACUUACCAUGGCAUAGGACUAGAGGGGGCCUCAAAGAUUAUUUAAAGAAAAACAAACCAAUGCCUUUAAGGCUUGUGACUCUGUAACUAGAGGUGAAGUUUGGCUGGAUGCAUUCAUUUAGCAACUAGUUACUUAUUGAGCUUUUACUGCAUCUCAGGCACUGCAGUGGAAACACAGGAUGAACUAGACAAUGUCCCUCCCUCUAGGUCUUCUAAAAAAAAGACCAGUACAUGAAAAAUAAUUGUAAAUUAUGAUACAAAACAAGGAGCAGAAUAGGGAAGAACUAAAGCUUGGGGCAGAAAUGAGGCUGGCUACUUUAGGUGGGAUGGCCAAGGAUAACAUCUCUCUGACAUUUGUGUUAAGAAUUAAAGCCAUAUAAAGUGCUUCCCAGGGUGCCAGACCAAUAUGGUAUAUUCUUCAUAAAUAUGCUACAUGAAGAGUGGGAAGAGCAAAAGAGCAGAAGAGCAUUCCAGCUGGAGGAGCAAACAUUUGCAAAAGUUCAAGAUGGGAAGAUCUCGGCCCUUUCCAGGACUUGAAAAAAGGCCCCUGGCUGGAGAGUCAUGAGAGAAGGGAAGCAGCUUCAGAUGAAUUCGGAGAGGUAGAAGCAGCCAGAUCCUCUAGAGCCUUGUAGGCCACAGUAAGGGGGUUGAGUUGUAAUGCAAGGCAGAGUUCUCAAGCUCUAUCAUGAAUCAGAAUCACCUGGAGAUUCAAUAGAGAUUGCUGGACCCCAUCCCUAGAGAUGGGGACCUUCUAAUAAGUUUGCAUGUGGUGCCGAUGCUACUGGGCCAGAGACCAGACUUUGAGAACCACUGCUGUAAGGCAGUGAGAACCCUAACAGAAGGAUGUUUCAUAUAAUUAAUUUGCAGGACUUAGUAACUGAUGGAGUGUAGGGUUAAAGAGGGAAAAGAAUCAAAGAUAAUUCUAAAGGUACAGUCCUGUGUGAUCAGGAGGUAAAACAUAUAGGAAAAAUUCUUGUUUUUUGAGACGGAGUCUCGCUCUGUCGCCCAGGCUGGAGUGCAGUGGCACAAUCUUGGCUCACUGCAAGCUCCGCUUCCCGAGUUCAUGCCAUUCUCCUGCCUCAGCCUCCCGAGUAGCUGGGACUACAGGCGCCCGCCACCACGCCUGGCUAAUUUUUUGUAUUUUUAGUAGAGAUGGGGUUUCACUGUGUUAGCCAGGAUGGUCUCAAUCUCCUGACCUCAUGAUCCACCCGUCUCGGCCUCCCAAAGUGCUGGGAUUACAGGCAUGAGACACUGCUCCCGGCCCGAAAAAUUCUUUAUUCAGGGCUGGAUGAUGAGAUGGUAUAACCAGCAGGAAUCUUCCUUGGGUUUCAGUAGGUGUGGGAAUUAACUCACAGAUCCAUGUGUGUGUAUGCAUUUUUUCUUAAACAGGUGGUAGAGAGGGUACAAAUAUCAGGGAGAAAGUCCACAGAAGCAGGAUAAGAUACUGUCAACCUGGGGUUCCUUCAGGCCUUCCCAGCCAAACCCUUCCCCCUGCAACUCAGGAUCAGCCACCUCAUUGACUUGCCCCACCCAAGGCCAAACCAAUAUUGACAGCAGCCUCAAUGCACCAGCAGGAGGGGUCUACAGUUAUUGCUGCCACAGGUCUUACACCAGAUGGCCCUCGGUGGGCCAGCCUGUUCUUGCCCAGUCUGUUCUUGCCCUGUUCUGACCAGUGGCAGUGCUGCCUUACCAGGGAUGCCCUAUCUCCACCUGAAUGAACCAGGUCUGGGUUUGCACUGCUCUGCCCCAGAAUGCCCCGCUGUUUUCACGUAGUCAGGCAGGUUCCCCAGCCUUAGUUCUACCAGAGCCAGCCUCCUCGCUUCCCCAUGCAUCAGUGCUGCUGAGAGUGAAUCCAAGUUACGGGAGUAACCUUGCUGAGCAGGAGGCCAAAACCAGUGAGUGACAUGAAGCAUCGUCCAUCCAAAAGAGAGGCCAAGAAAGCAUGGAAAGGACAGUGUCAUGGAGGCCUAGCAGGAGACAAACUUUUAAAAGAGGCAGAGAGAUCUAAAUACAUCCAAACUGUUGAAGCGUAAAGCAUUAGAAAAAAAUAUGAUUUCUCAACAAGUUAUGACACCUUCAUAGAGAACAGUUAUACAGGAAUGAGUGGGUGGAAGAAAAUAGCAACCACAGCCCAAUAAUGCAGAUCUAAUGUUAUUAGGUUAAAUACUACACAAGUAAUUACUCAGUGAUGAAAAUUAUUAAUUGUGCACAUGAUGCUCACUCUAUGCCCUGGGUGUUUCUGUUCCUGCUUGAAUAGUGGAAUAAUUAGCAGAUAACUGCGCUAUUAAUUAUGCCAAAGCUUGCUUUGAGAUAGACUAAAAGGCCAAACAUGUAGGAUGAGGAGGAGCUAUGUGUUCUGUUCAUCUUUGUGCCCUGAGAAGAGCAGAUGGAAAGCUUGAGGUCAACCUGGGCCCACAGCUGGCCAGGUAGACUGAAGUUCUGUCAUGCCCUGCCUUGAAAGGGAACCAGAGUGCCUAUGCAGGAAGCCCACGCACAUAGCACUUAGGCAUAGCAGGGGGUUAAAGGUGUUUUCAAGUUCAAGUCAUGACACAUUUAUAAGCCAAAGCCCCAAGGGCCAGUAUUUUCCAAUCUCUUCCUCCACCAUCCUUGGCCAUAUGGUAAACAUUUCUCUUUCCUUUCCCCAUUGACACCAACAAGUUCAUCUCACAUGGGUAAGACUCAGACAAAUCCCAUAGCUUUUUACACGUAGAUUUUCCACAAAGCGAAUCCCGGCAAACGAUAUACAGAACUCCUAGCUUAUCUUGCCAUGGGAUGAGAUAAGAUGGUAAGAAGUCAUCCUGUGGCCAGGUGUGGUGGCUUAUGCCUGUCAUCCCAGCACUUUGGAAGGCUGAGGGGGGAGGAUUGCUUGAGCCCAGUAGUUUGAAAACAGCCUGGGCAACAUGAUGAAACCUUGUCUCUAACAACAACAACAACAACAAAAUUAGCUGAGUGUGGUGGCACAUGCCUGUAGUCCCUGCUACUCGGAGGCUGAGGCAGGAGAAUCACUCAAGCCUGGGAUAUGGAGGUCACAGUGAGCCAAGAGGGGAUCACUGCACUCCAGCCUGGGCAACAGAGUGAGACCCUGUCUCAAAAAAAAAAAAAAAA